GCCCAGCCCCGGGCUCCGGGCGGGAAGUGGGCGAGCGCGACGGUGCGGGGCGCGCGGGCGACGGGCCAGCGGGAUGGGAGCAGGGUCCCCCGGCGGCCCGCAGCCUCGGGAGCCGCGCUGAAGCCGGGGGCGGGACCAGCGCGGAGCCGACAUGUGUCUGCGCCUCGGAGGCCUGAGUGUGGGCGACUUCCGGAAGGUGCUGAUGAAGACAGGCCUGGUGCUGGUGGUGCUGGGCCAUGUGAGCUUCAUCACAGCUGCCCUGUUCCAUGGCACAGUGCUGCGCUACGUGGGCACCCCUCAAGAUGCGGUGGCUCUGCAGUACUGCGUGGUCAACAUCCUCUCUGUCACUUCCGCCAUCGUGGUCAUCACUUCAGGCAUCGCAGCCAUCGUGUUGUCACGCUACCUCCCUAGCACCCCCCUGCGCUGGACAGUGUUUAGCUCGAGCGUGGCCUGUGCUCUCCUUUCUCUGACCUGUGCCCUCGGCCUCUUGGCCUCCAUCGCCAUGACCUUUGCCACCCAGGGCAAGGCACUGCUGGCUGCCUGCACUUUUGGGAGCUCUGAACUACUGGCCCUCGCACCUGACUGUCCCUUCGACCCCACACGCAUUUAUAGCUCCAGCCUGUGCCUCUGGGGCAUCGCCCUAGUGCUCUGCGUGGCGGAGAACGUGUUUGCUGUACGCUGUGCUCAGCUCACCCACCAGCUGCUGGAGCUGAGGCCCUGGUGGGGGAAAAGCAGCCACCACAUGGAGGAGACCCAGGCUGAGAACCAGUGGGUCUGGCAGCCUCCUGUGUCUCUGCAGAUGCGGGAGAACCCAGAGCUGGUGGAGGGCCGUGACCUGCUGAGCUGCACCAGCUCUGAGCCUCUGACCCUCUGAGAGAUGAUGUCCUGCCCAGGCCCGAUGGCCACUAGGACCCUGCAAGCAACUCUGCUCUGUGACCAGGCCAGGAUUCCUGGAGCUGGCCUGAGAGGGCUCAAUGGACCCUCGGGGACCCAAGUGGGGCUUUCAACCCUCUCCCCCACCACCCAGCCCACUGCACUGAAAUGAGACUUUAUUCUGAAAUUAUUAAAAAGAACAGAGAUGCUC